GGAGUUUAUUCAUAACGCGCUCUCCAAGUAUACGUGGCAAUGCGUUGCUGGGUUAUUUUAAUCAUUCUAGGCAUCGUUUUCCUCCUUAUGCCUCUAUCAUUCCUCCCUAUCUACACUAACAUCCCACGCUCUGAACGCGCGCCCAUUAAUACCCUUCUUUCCUCCACUCUCCCUGGGACUCUUGAUCAAAGCGCGGCCCUUUCCCCAGCCUUAGCGAGGCGCCCUGCAGCCUGGUACGCGCGUGGCGUGGCGGUGGGCGCGCAGUGCGUUCUCGGUGUGGAGGGCAGCUGUUCCGCCUGCGAUGAUUUAUACUCACAGGACAAGGAUGCGGUUUGUCAAACAGUACUGCUACGGAGGAGCAGCAGAGAAAGGGAGAGGGUUUGAGAGGGAGCAAAAGAAAAUGGUAGGCGCGCGUAGUUAAUUCAUGCGGCUCUCUUACUCUGUUUACAUCCUAGAGCUAGAGUGCUCGGCUGCCCGGCUGAGUCUCCUCCCCACCUUCCCCACCCUCCCCACCCUCCCCAUAAGCGCCCCUCCCGGGUUCCCAAAGCAGAGGGCGUGGGGGAAAAGAAAAAAGAUCCUCUCUCGCUAAUCUCCGCCCACCGGCCCUUUAUAAUGCGAGGGUCUGGACGGCUGAGGACCCCCGAGCUGUGCUGCUCGCGGCCGCCACCGCCGGGCCCCGGCCGUCCCUGGCUCCCCUCCUGCCUCGAGAAGGGCAGGGCUUCUCAGAGGCUUGGCGGGAAAAAGAACGGAGGGAGGGAUCGCGCUGAGUAUAAAAGCCGGUUUUCGGGGCUUUAUCUAACUCGCUGUAGUAAUUCCAGCGAGAGGCAGAGGGAGCGAGCGGGCGGCCGGCUAGGGUGGAAGAGCCGGGCGAGCAGAGCUGCGCUGCGGGCGUCCUGGGAAGGGAGAUCCGGAGCGAAUAGGGGGCUUCGCCUCUGGCCCAGCCCUCCCGCUGAUCCCCCAGCCAGCGGUCCGCAACCCUUGCCGCAUCCACGAAACUUUGCCCAUAGCAGCGGGCGGGCACUUUGCACUGGAACUUACAACACCCGAGCAAGGACGCGACUCUCCCGACGCGGGGAGGCUAUUCUGCCCAUUUGGGGACACUUCCCCGCCGCUGCCAGGACCCGCUUCUCUGAAAGGCUCUCCUUGCAGCUGCUUAGACGCUGGAUUUUUUUCGGGUAGUGGAAAACCAGCCUCCCGCGACGAUGCCCCUCAACGUUAGCUUCACCAACAGGAACUAUGACCUCGACUACGACUCGGUGCAGCCGUAUUUCUACUGCGACGAGGAGGAGAACUUCUACCAGCAGCAGCAGCAGAGCGAGCUGCAGCCCCCGGCGCCCAGCGAGGAUAUCUGGAAGAAAUUCGAGCUGCUGCCCACCCCGCCCCUGUCCCCUAGCCGCCGCUCCGGGCUCUGCUCGCCCUCCUACGUUGCGGUCACACCCUUCUCCCUUCGGGGAGACAACGACGGCGGUGGCGGGAGCUUCUCCACGGCCGACCAGCUGGAGAUGGUGACCGAGCUGCUGGGAGGAGACAUGGUGAACCAGAGUUUCAUCUGCGACCCGGACGACGAGACCUUCAUCAAAAACAUCAUCAUCCAGGACUGUAUGUGGAGCGGCUUCUCGGCCGCCGCCAAGCUCGUCUCAGAGAAGCUGGCCUCCUACCAGGCUGCGCGCAAAGACAGCGGCAGCCCGAACCCCGCCCGCGGCCACAGCGUCUGCUCCACCUCCAGCUUGUACCUGCAGGAUCUGAGCGCCGCCGCCUCAGAGUGCAUCGACCCCUCGGUGGUCUUCCCCUACCCUCUCAACGACAGCAGCUCGCCCAAGUCCUGCGCCUCGCAAGACUCCAGCGCCUUCUCUCCGUCCUCGGAUUCUCUGCUCUCCUCGACGGAGUCCUCCCCGCAGGGCAGCCCCGAGCCCCUGGUGCUCCAUGAGGAGACACCGCCCACCACCAGCAGCGACUCUGAGGAGGAACAAGAAGAUGAGGAAGAAAUCGAUGUUGUUUCUGUGGAAAAGAGGCAGGCUCCUGGCAAAAGGUCAGAGUCUGGAUCACCUUCUGCUGGAGGCCACAGCAAACCUCCUCACAGCCCACUGGUCCUCAAGAGGUGCCACGUCUCCACACAUCAGCACAACUACGCAGCGCCUCCCUCCACUCGGAAGGACUAUCCUGCUGCCAAGAGGGUCAAGUUGGACAGUGUCAGAGUCCUGAGACAGAUCAGCAACAACCGAAAAUGCACCAGCCCCAGGUCCUCGGACACCGAGGAGAAUGUCAAGAGGCGAACACACAACGUCUUGGAGCGCCAGAGGAGGAACGAGCUAAAACGGAGCUUUUUUGCCCUGCGUGACCAGAUCCCGGAGUUGGAAAACAAUGAAAAGGCCCCCAAGGUAGUUAUCCUUAAAAAAGCCACAGCAUACAUCCUGUCCGUCCAAGCAGAGGAGCAAAAGCUCAUUUCUGAAGAGGACUUGUUGCGGAAACGACGAGAACAGUUGAAACACAAACUUGAACAGCUACGGAACUCUUGUGCGUAAGGAAAAGUAAGGAAAACGAUUCCUUCUAACAGAAAUGUCCUGAGCAAUCACCUAUGAACUUGUUUCAAAUGCAUGAUCAAAUGCAACCUCACAACCUUGGCUGAGUCUUGAGACUGAAAGAUUUAGCCAUAAUGUAAACUGCCUCAAAUUGGACUUUGGGCAUAAAAGAACUUUUUUAUGCUUACCAUCUUUUUUUUUUCUUUAACAGAUUUGUAUUUAAGAAUUGUUUUUAAAAAAUUUUAAGAUUUACACAAUGUUUCUCUGUAAAUAUUGCCAUUAAAUGUAAAUAACUUUAAUAAAACGUUUAUAGCAGUUACACAGAAUUUCAAUCCUAGUAUAUAGUACCUAGUAUUAUAGGUACUAUAAACCCUAAUUUUUUUUAUUUAAGUACAUUUUGCUUUUUAAAGUUGAUUUUUUUCUAUUGUUUUUAGAAAAAAUAAAAUAACUGGCAAAUAUAUCAUUGAGCCAAAUCUUAAGUUGUGAAUGUUUUGUUUCGUUUCUUCCCCCUCCCAACCACCACCAUCCCUGUUUGUUUUCAUCAAUUGCCCCUUCAGAGGGUGGUCUUAAGAAAGGCAAGAGUUUUCCUCUGUUGAAAUGGGUCUGGGGGCCUUAAGGUCUUUAAGUUCUUGGAGGUUCUAAGAUGCUUCCUGGAGACUAUGAUAACAGCCAGAGUUGACAGUUAGAAGGAAUGGCAGAAGGCAGGUGAGAAGGUGAGAGGUAGGCAAAGGAGAUACAAGAGGUCAAAGGUAGCAGUUAAGUACACAAAGAGGCAUAAGGACUGGGGAGUUGGGAGGAAGGUGAGGAAGAAACUCCUGUUACUUUAGUUAACCAGUGCCAGUCCCCUGCUCACUCCAAACCCAGGAAUUCUGCCCAGUUGAUGGGGACACGGUGGGAACCAGCUUCUGCUGCCUUCACAACCAGGCGCCAGUCCUGUCCAUGGGUUAUCUCGCAAACCCCAGAGGAUCUCUGGGAGGAAUGCUACUAUUAACCCUAUUUCACAAACAAGGAAAUAGAAGAGCUCAAAGAGGUUAUGUAACUUAUCUGUAGCCACGCAGAUAAUACAAAGCAGCAAUCUGGACCCAUUCUGUUCAAAACACUUAACCCUUCGCUAUCAUGCCUUGGUUCAUCUGGGUCUAAUGUGCUGAGAUCAAGAAGGUUUAGGACCUAAUGGACAGACUCAAGUCAUAACAAUGCUAAGCUCUAUUUGUGUCCCAAGCACUCCUAAGCAUUUUAUCCCUAACUCUACAUCAACCCCAUGAAGGAGAUACUGUUGAUUUCCCCAUAUUAGAAGUAGAGAGGGAAGCUGAGGCACACAAAGACUCAUCCACAUGCCCAAGAUUCACUGAUAGGGAAAAGUGGAAGCGAGAUUUGAACCCAGGCUGUUUACUCCUAACCUGUCCAAGCCACCUCUCAGACGACGGUAGGAAUCAGCUGGCUGCUUGUGAGUACAGGAGUUACAGUCCAGUGGGUUAUGUUUUUUAAGUCUCAACAUCUAAGCCUGGUCAGGCAUCAGUUCCCCUUUUUUUGUGAUUUAUUUUGUUUUUAUUUUGUUGUUCAUUGUUUAAUUUUUCCUUUUACAAUGAGAAGGUCACCAUCUUGACUCCUACCUUAGCCAUUUGUUGAAUCAGACUCAUGACGGCUCCUGGGAAGAAGCCAGUUCAGAUCAUAAAAUAAAACAUAUUUAUUCUUUGUCAUGGGAGUCAUUAUUUUAGAAACUACAAACUCUCCUUGCUUCCAUCCUUUUUUACAUACUCAUGACACAUGCUCAUCCUGAGUCCUUGAAAAGGUAUUUUUGAACAUGUGUAUUAAUUAUAAGCCUCUGAAAACCUAUGGCCCAAACCAGAAAUGAUGUUGAUUAUAUAGGUAAAUGAAGGAUGCUAUUGCUGUUCUAAUUACCUCAUUGUCUCAGUCUCAAAGUAGGUCUUCAGCUCCCUGUACUUUGGGAUUUUAAUCUACCACCACCCAUAAAUCAAUAAAUAAUUACUUUCUUUGA